ACGGAAGUGAAACUCUAAGAAAUGAGAUGGAGAAGUACGAGCGGAUCCGAGUGGUGGGGAGAGGUGCCUUCGGGAUUGUGCACCUGUGCCUGCGAAAGGCUGACCAGAAGCUGGUGAUCAUCAAGCAGAUUCCAGUGGAACAGAUGACCAAGGAAGAGCGGCAGGCAGCCCAGAAUGAGUGCCAGGUCCUCAAGCUGCUCAACCACCCCAAUGUCAUUGAGUACUACGAGAACUUCCUGGAAGACAAAGCCCUUAUGAUCGCCAUGGAAUAUGCACCAGGCGGCACUCUGGCUGAGUUCAUCCAAAAGCGCUGUAAUUCCCUGCUGGAGGAGGAGACCAUCCUGCACUUCUUCGUGCAGAUCCUGCUUGCACUGCAUCAUGUGCACACCCACCUCAUCCUGCACCGAGACCUCAAGACCCAGAACAUCCUGCUUGACAAACACCGCAUGGUCGUCAAGAUCGGUGAUUUCGGCAUCUCCAAGAUCCUUAGCAGCAAGAGCAAGGCCUACACGGUGGUGGGUACCCCAUGCUAUAUCUCCCCUGAGCUGUGUGAGGGCAAGCCCUACAACCAGAAGAGUGACAUCUGGGCCCUGGGCUGUGUCCUCUACGAGCUGGCCAGCCUCAAGAGGGCUUUCGAGGCUGCGAACUUGCCAGCACUGGUGCUGAAGAUCAUGAGUGGCACCUUUGCACCUAUCUCUGACCGGUACAGCCCUGAGCUUCGCCAGCUGGUCCUGAGUCUACUCAGCCUGGAGCCUGCCCAGCGGCCACCACUCAGCCACAUCAUGGCACAGCCCCUCUGCAUCCGUGCCCUCCUCAACCUCCACACCGACGUGGGCAGUGUCCGCAUGCGGAGGGCAGAGAAGUCCGUGGCCCCCAGCAACACAGGGAGCAGGACCACCAGUGUCCGCUGCAGAGGUAUCCCCCGGGGACCUGUGAGGCCAGCCAUCCCACCACCACUGUCGUCAGUGUAUGCCUGGGGUGGUGGGCUGGGCACCCCCCUGCGGCUGCCAAUGCUCAACACAGAGGUGGUCCAGGUGGCAGCUGGGCGCACGCAGAAAGCCGGCGUCACGCGCUCUGGGCGUCUCAUCCUGUGGGAGGCCCCACCCCUAGGUGCAGGCGGAGGCAGUCUCCUUCCUGGGGCAGUGGAGCAGCCACAGCCCCAGUUCAUCUCGCGUUUCCUGGAGGGCCAGUCGGGUGUGACCAUCAAGCACGUGGCCUGUGGGGACUUCUUCACUGCCUGCCUGACUGACAGAGGCAUCAUCAUGACAUUCGGCAGCGGCAGCAAUGGGUGCCUAGGCCAUGGCAGCCUCACUGACAUCAGCCAGCCCACCAUUGUGGAGGCUUUGCUGGGCUAUGAAAUGGUGCAGGUGGCCUGUGGGGCCUCUCACGUGCUGGCCCUGUCCACUGAGCGAGAACUAUUUGCCUGGGGCCGUGGAGACAGCGGCAGACUGGGGCUAGGCACCAGGGAGUCCCACAGCUGCCCCCAGCAGGUGCCCAUGCCCCCAGGACAGGAAGCUCAGCGAGUUGUAUGUGGUAUCGAUUCCUCCAUGAUCCUCACUGUGCCUGGCCAAGCCCUAGCCUGUGGGAGCAACAGGUUCAACAAGCUGGGCCUGGACCACCUCUCCCUGGGGGAGGAGCCUGUCCCCCACCAGCAAGUGGAGGAGGCCCUGAGCUUCACACUACUAGGCUCUGCACCCCUGGACCAGGAGCCUCUGCUGAGUAUAGACCUGGGCACUGCUCACUCAGCUGCUGUGACUGCCUCGGGUGAUUGCUACACUUUUGGCAGCAAUCAGCACGGACAGUUGGGCACCAAUACUCGCCGAGGCAGUCGGGCACCCUGUAAGGUCCAAGGCCUUGAGGGCAUCAAGAUGGCAAUGGUAGCCUGUGGGGAUGCCUUCACUGUAGCUAUUGGGGCAGAGAGCGAAGUGUACUCUUGGGGCAAAGGGGCGCGAGGUCGAUUGGGAAGGAGGGAUGAGGAUGCCGGACUCCCUCGGCCAGUGCAGUUGGAUGAGACACACCCUUACACGGUGACUUCCGUGUCCUGUUGCCAUGGAAACACCCUCCUGGCUGUUCGAUCGGUCACAGAUGAGCCGGUCCCCCCCUGAGGCACCCGGAUUCACCUCUGGACCACCCUGAUAUUGCUUCUCCUCUGAAUGCUCUGAAAAGUGCAGGUGCCCAAGGCAUGACUUGCAGCUGUCUCCUGGAUUGUGUCAUCAUGGGGUAUCAGGGCUGGCAAAACCCCUGCUCUGCUUUUGGCCUUGGAUAUGGAAACCUCAACCACUUUGUUCUCCUACCACCUCUUUGCCCUUCCUACCCCUUCCUCCCUUCAGUCAGUGUCCCCAGGGUCCAGCCUGGCUAGAGUUAGAAGGCAGACCUAGCCUUUGGAAGCAGGGUGGCCUCCAGAGCCUUGCCAUAAAAAGGCUGAAGGCAGCCGGGCGCAGUGGCUCACGCCUGUAAUCCCAGCACUUUGGGAGGCUGAGGCGGGCGGAUCACGAGGUCAGGAGAUCGAGACCAUCCUGGCUAACGUGGUGAAACCCCAUCUCUACUAAAAAUACAAAAAAAUUAGCUGGGCGUGGUGGCACGCGCCUGUAGUCCCAGCUGCUCAGGAGGCUGAGGCAGGAGAAUGGCGUAAACCCCUCCAGCCUGGGCGACAGAACCAGACUCCGUCUCAAAAAAAAAAAAAAAACAAAAAAGGCUGAAGGCAGCUGUAGCUCCACACAGACCCUACCCUUUCCCCUAGCCCAGUUAGAAAAUAAGUCUGGGCCGGCGGCGGUGGCUCACACCUGCAUAGGCAGUGCUUUGGCCAGGAGGAUCCCUUGAUCCCUUGUGGCCAGGAGUUGGGAGACCAGCCUGGGGACCAUAGCGAGACCGCUGUCUCCACCAAAAAAAAAAAAAAAGAAGAAAAUAAGGCUGGGUGCGGUGGCUCACGCCUGUAAUUCCAGCACUUUGGGAGGCCAAGGCGGGCGGAUCACUUGAGGUCAGUAGACUGAGGCCAGCCUGGCCAACAUGGUGAAACCCCGUCUCUACUAAAAAUACAAAAAUUAACCAGGCAUGGUGACGGGCGCCUGUAAUCCCAGCUACUCUGGAGGCUAAGGCAAGAGAAUCCCUUGAACCCGGGAGGUGAAGUUUGCAGUGAGCCGAGAUCGCACCACUGCACUCCAGCCUGGAUGACAGAGCAAGUCUCCCUCUCAAAAAAAAAAAAAAAAAAAAAAAAAAAAAAGUAUUUGGUGCUUACCGGGACUCUAUCUCCAUACUUUGGAGCAGGGCAAGCCAGGGCCUGCCUGGACUGGCCAUUAGGCCUGCCUAGCUUCUGCAUAGCCCGGGGCUGGGCGGUCCCCGGGAGUGCUGCCACCUCCCCUACACUUUCAUCCUGAGGCAGGAUUUGCUAGACGUCGGCUUGCCUCUCUUCCCCAGCAGGAGGGCAGGAGUCACUAAGUGCUGCAGAAAAGAUCCGCGCUGGAGAUUGCCCGUCCCCCCCAUGCCUUUCCCCAGAAACAGUUGAGAGAAUGGGUAGCUGGUGGGACCAGACCGGUUUCCCAGAGGACAGGAAGGCCAAUAAAAAUAUCAGCUGCC